AUCAAUCAUCCGAGAACCUUGGAGGGUGGACAGUGCCCCUUUUACAGAUGAGAAAACUGAGGCUUGAAGGGGAGAAGCAGCUGCCUCUGGCGGCAUGGCUUCUGGCUGCAGGAUGCCCAUGGAGUUCGUGGUGACCCUAGGCCUGUGUCUCGGCUUCCUUUGCUGAACUUGAACAGGAAGAUGGCAGUGGGGGCCAGUGGUCUAGAAGGAGAUAAGAUGGCUGGUGCCAUGCCUCUGCAACUCCUCCUGUUGCUGAUCCUACUGGGCCCUGGCAACAGCUUGCAGCUGUGGGACACCUGGGCAGAUGAAGCCGAGAAAGCCUUGGGUCCCCUGCUUGCCCGGGACCGGAGACAGGCCACCGAAUAUGAGUACCUAGAUUAUGAUUUCCUGCCAGAAACGGAGCCUCCAGAAAUGCUGAGGAACAGCACUGACACCACUCCUCUGACUGGGCCUGGAACCCCUGAGUCUACCACUGUGGAGCCUGCUGCAAGGCGUUCUACUGGCCUGGAUGCAGGAGGGGCAGUCACAGAGCUGACCACGGAGCUGGCCAACAUGGGGAACCUGUCCACGGAUUCAGCAGCUAUGGAGAUACAGACCACUCAACCAGCAGCCACGGAGGCACAGACCACUCAACCAGUGCCCACGGAGGCACAGACCACUCCACUGGCAGCCACAGAGGCACAGACAACUCGACUGACGGCCACGGAGGCACAGACCACUCCACUGGCAGCCACAGAGGCACAGACCACUCCACCAGCAGCCACGGAAGCACAGACCACUCAACCCACAGGCCUGGAGGCACAGACCACUGCACCAGCAGCCAUGGAGGCACAGACCACUGCACCAGCAGCCAUGGAAGCACAGACCACUCCACCAGCAGCCAUGGAGGCACAGACCACUCAAACCACAGCCAUGGAGGCACAGACCACUGCACCAGAAGCCACGGAGGCACAGACCACUCAACCCACAGCCACGGAGGCACAGACCACUCCACUGGCAGCCAUGGAGGCCCUGUCCACAGAACCCAGUGCCACAGAGGCCCUGUCCAUGGAACCUACUACCAAAAGAGGUCUGUUCAUACCCUUUUCUGUGUCCUCUGUUACUCACAAGGGCAUUCCCAUGGCAGCCAGCAAUUUGUCCGUCAACUACCCAGUGGGGGCCCCAGACCACAUCUCUGUGAAGCAGUGCCUGCUGGCCAUCCUAAUCUUGGCGCUGGUGGCCACUAUCUUCUUCGUGUGCACUGUGGUGCUGGCGGUCCGCCUCUCCCGCAAGGGCCACAUGUACCCCGUGCGUAAUUACUCCCCCACCGAGAUGGUCUGCAUCUCAUCCCUGUUGCCUGAUGGGGGUGAGGGGCCCUCUGCCACAGCCAAUGGGGGCCUGUCCAAGGCCAAGAGCCCGGGCCUGACGCCAGAGCCCAGGGAGGACCGUGAGGGGGAUGACCUCACCCUGCACAGCUUCCUCCCUUAGCUCACUCUGCCAUCUGUUUUGGCAAGACCCCACCUCCACGGGCUCUCCUGGGCCACCCCUGAGUGCCCAGACCCCAUUCCACAGCUCUGGGCUUCCUCGGAGACCCCUGGGGAUGGGGAUCUUCAGGGAAGGAACUCUGGCCACCCAAACAGGACAAGAGCAGCCUGGGGCCAAGCAGACGGGCAAGUGGAGCCACCUCUUUCCUCCCUCCGCGGAUGAAGCCCAGCCACAUUUCAGCCGAGGUCCAAGGCAGGAGGCCAUUUACUUGAGACAGAUUCUCUCCUUUUUCCUGUCCCCCAUCUUCUCUGGGUCCCUCUAACAUCUCCCAUGGCUCUCCCCGCUUCUCCUGGUCACUGGAGUCUCCUCCCCAUGUACCCAAGGAAGAUGGAGCUCCCCCAUCCCACACGCACUGCACUGCCAUUGUCUUUUGGUUGCCAUGGUCACCAAACAGGAAGUGGACAUUCUAAGGGAGGAGUACUGAAGAGUGACGGACUUCUGAGGCUGUUUCCUGCUGCUCCUCUGACUUGGGGCAGCUUGGGUCUUCUUGGGCACCUCUCUGGGAAAACCCAGGGUGAGGUUCAGCCUGUGAGGGCUGGGAUGGGUUUCGUGGGCCCAAGGGCAGACCUUUCUUUGGGACUGUGUGGACCAAGGAGCUUCCAUCUAGUGACAAGUGACCCCCAGCUAUCGCCUCUUGCCUUCCCCUGUGGCCACUUUCCAGGGUGGACUCUGUCUUGUUCACUGCAGUAUCCCAACUGCAGGUCCAGUGCAGGCAAUAAAUAUGUGAUGGACAAACGAUAGCGGAAUCCUUCAAGGUUUCAAGGCUGUCUCCUUCAGGCAGCCUUCCCGGAAUUCUCCAUCCCUCAGUGCAGGAUGGGGGCUGGUCCUCAGCUGUCUGCCCUCAGCCCCUGGCCCCCCAGGAAGCCUCUUUCAUGGGCUGUUAGGUUGACUUCAGUUUUGCCUCUUGGACAACAGGGGGUCUUGUACAUCCUUGGGUGACCAGGAAAAGUUCAGGCUAUGGGGGGCCAAAGGGAGGGCUGCCCCUUCCCCACCAGUGACCACUUUAUUCCACUUCCUCCAUUACCCAGUUUUGGCCCACAGAGUUUGGUCCCCCCCAAACCUCGGACCAAUAUCCCUCUAAACAUCAAUCUAUCCUCCUGUUAAAGAAAAAAAAAAA